AGCGGAAGUGUCCUUCUUUCCUUUUUGCUGGUAGGGCCGGGUGGUUGCUGCCGGUAAGUAGAAGCUUGGGUUGAAUCUUUCAAUCCGCUGCCAUCCGCGGCUUGGGGGUCGAAGGUCCGGGCGGCGCCGGGUGCAUUCCUUCCCUAGGUCUCUGGCGGCUACGUAUCCGAUCCUGUCCUGCGAGCAGGGCCCUCGGGCGGCCUUGACCAAGGCGACAGUGAACACAGUCUGAAGUUCCGGCCCAAGACCUGGGCUUGCUGGCAGGAGUCAGCUCUGGGCAUCUUUGGCUUUACGGAUUUUUAAGUGGCCCUUUCUCCUUGCUCUCUGCAGAAAUGGGCAAGUUCAUGAAACCUGGGAAGGUGGUGCUUGUCCUGGCUGGACGCUACUCCGGACGCAAAGCUGUCAUCGUGAAGAACAUUGAUGAUGGCACCUCAGAUCGCCCCUACAGCCAUGCUCUGGUGGCUGGAAUUGACCGCUACCCCCGCAAAGUGACAGCUGCCAUGGGCAAGAAGAAGAUCGCCAAGAGAUCAAAGAUAAAAUCUUUUGUGAAAGUGUAUAACUACAAUCACCUAAUGCCCACAAGGUACUCUGUGGAUAUCCCCUUGGACAAAACUGUCGUCAAUAAGGAUGUCUUCAGAGAUCCUGCUCUUAAACGCAAGGCCCGACGGGAGGCCAAGGUCAAGUUUGAAGAGAGAUACAAGACAGGCAAGAACAAGUGGUUCUUCCAGAAACUGCGGUUUUAGAUGCUUUGUUUUGAUCAUUAAAAAUUAUAAAGAAAAAAA